GGAGAGCAGCGCACCGGCAUGGGCAGGCGGCCGGCGGCGGAGGGCGGCUGAGGGCUGCUGAGGGUACGCGCAGCGGCCUCUCGUCGCCCUGCACGUGCCUCGCCAGGCAGUGCGCCUGCUCGCAGCGAGGACCUAGCCCUCUGGUUGCAGAGACCCGGUGCCGCAGCAGCGGCGGGUGGCUGUCGCUGCCCUGCCCUGCACGGGGCAGGGCGGAGCGGGCUGAGCAGCCCGGGCGCGAUGCGUUGAGCGCUCGGAGGGCCAACCGCCGGUCCCCUUGGCGGCAACCGGCGGCACCCAUGGAACCACUGGGCAACUGGAGGAGCCUGCGGGCGCCACUGCCUCCGAUGCUGUUGCUGCUGCUCCUGCAGGUGGCGGGGCCCGUGGGCGCCCUGGCGGAGACCUUGCUGAACGCGCCGAGGGCCAUGGGCACCAGUUCCAGCCCGCCUAGCCCUGCGAGCGUGGUGGCUCCCGGAACGACGCUGUUCGAGGAGAGCCGGCUGCCUGUGUUUACGCUGGAUUACCCCCACGUGCAGAUCCCCUUCGAGAUCACCCUUUGGAUCCUGCUGGCCUCCCUGGCCAAGAUUGGCUUCCAUCUGUAUCACAAGUUGCCCACAAUAGUGCCUGAGAGCUGCCUUCUUAUAAUGGUUGGACUUCUACUAGGUGGGAUUAUUUUUGGUGUUGAUGAGAAGUCUCCCCCUGCAAUGAAGACUGAUGUAUUUUUCUUGUACCUCCUCCCACCCAUCGUGCUGGAUGCCGGCUAUUUCAUGCCCACUCGCCCAUUCUUUGAGAACAUUGGCACGAUUUUCUGGUAUGCUGUGGUAGGGACACUUUGGAAUUCCAUUGGCAUUGGGGUGUCUUUGUUUGGUAUCUGCCAGAUCGAAGCAUUCGGCCUCAGCGACAUCACUUUGCUCCAGAACCUGCUCUUUGGCAGCUUAAUCUCAGCUGUCGAUCCUGUGGCUGUGCUUGCUGUCUUUGAGAACAUUCACGUCAAUGAGCAGCUCUACAUCCUGGUCUUUGGAGAGUCCCUGCUGAAUGAUGCAGUAACAGUGGUCCUGUACAACUUGUUCAAGUCGUUUUGCCAGAUGAAAACCAUUGAGACCAUUGAUGUGUUUGCAGGAAUCGCCAACUUCUUUGUUGUGGGAAUCGGUGGGGUGCUGAUUGGCAUCUUCUUGGGCUUUAUAGCGGCAUUUACUACUCGAUUCACCCAUAAUAUCCGAGUGAUCGAGCCACUGUUUGUUUUCCUGUACAGUUAUUUGUCCUACAUCACAGCUGAAAUGUUUCACCUCUCAGGCAUCAUGGCAAUCACUGCUUGUGCAAUGACUAUGAAUAAGUACGUAGAAGAAAAUGUAUCUCAGAAAUCCUACACGACCAUCAAGUACUUCAUGAAGAUGCUGAGCAGUGUCAGCGAAACCUUGAUCUUCAUCUUCAUGGGUGUGUCUACCGUGGGCAAGAACCACGAGUGGAACUGGGCCUUCGUCUGCUUCACCCUGGCCUUCUGCCUCAUGUGGCGAGCCCUGGGUGUUUUUGUCCUGACUCAGGUCAUUAAUAGGUUCCGGACCAUUCCCCUGACCUUUAAGGACCAGUUCAUCAUUGCCUAUGGAGGACUUCGAGGUGCCAUCUGUUUUGCGUUAGUGUUUCUCCUUCCUGCUGCUGUGUUUCCUCGGAAAAAAUUGUUUAUUACGGCUGCCAUUGUUGUCAUAUUCUUUACUGUCUUCAUUCUGGGAAUAACUAUUCGACCACUGGUGGAGUUUCUUGAUGUCAAGAGGUCCAAUAAGAAACAACAAGCUGUCAGUGAAGAAAUCUAUUGUCGGUUGUUUGAUCAUGUGAAGACUGGAAUUGAAGAUGUUUGUGGACAUUGGGGUCACAACUUUUGGAGAGACAAGUUUAAGAAGUUUGAUGAUAAAUAUCUGCGGAAGCUUUUGAUUCGGGAAAACCAACCAAAGUCAAGUAUUGUAUCUUUAUAUAAAAAGCUUGAAAUAAAACAUGCCAUUGAGAUGGCAGAGACUGGGAUGAUAAGUACUGUCCCUACAUUUGCAUCUCUAAAUGAUUGUCGUGAAGAAAAAAUAAGGAAGGUCACGUCCAGUGAAACUGAUGAAAUUCGAGAACUCUUAUCAAGAAAUCUCUAUCAAAUCCGUCAGCGAACUUUAUCCUACAACAGACACAGUCUGACAGCCGACACAAGUGAGAGACAAGCCAAGGAGAUUCUGAUUCGCCGGCGACACAGUUUGCGAGAAAGCAUUAGGAAGGACAGCAGCUUGAAUCGAGAACACAGGGCUUCCACUUCAACCUCCCGAUAUUUAUCCUUACCUAAAAAUACGAAGCUUCCAGAAAAGCUACAAAAGAGGAGGACUAUUUCUAUUGCAGAUGGCAAUAGCAGCGACUCAGACGCAGAUGCCGGGACCACCGUGCUCAAUUUGCAGCCCAGAGCCAGGCGCUUCUUGCCAGAACAGUUCUCCAAGAAAUCCCCCCAGUCCUAUAAAAUGGAAUGGAAGAAUGAGGUAGAUGUUGAUUCUGGCCGAGAUAUGCCCAGCACCCCCCCAACACCCCACAGCAGAGAAAAGGGCACCCAGACGUCAGGCUUACUACAGCAGCCCCUUCUCUCUAAAGACCAGUCUGGCUCAGAGAGGGAAGACAGUUUGACUGAAGGCAUCCCGCCCAAGCCGCCACCACGGCUGGUCUGGAGGGCAUCGGAACCUGGAAGCCGGAAAGCCCGAUUUGGGAGUGAGAAGCCUUAAGAGAAGCAGCGAAAGCAGAUCUGAGUGUCUGACCCAGGACAGCUGUGGUUUGUCACUCUGAAACCUGAUGCAACAGUGGAAUCCAUGUAAAACUCUCUGUGCAUCUAAAUACUUCUGGAGGGCGACAGAUUCAUGCCACGGAUAAAUGAGGCAAAUCCGAAGAAAAGGAAAAUCGAAUAAAAAAUAGUCCCACAAAAUACCUUUUGUGACUAAUGGGUAGCAAUCGUAUUAUUUGCUGGCCUGAAGAGAAAAAAUGGUAAUGUGUGCCUUUAUUGAACUUGAAUGACAGAACUUGAAAUUUUUAACACAUCCUUCUUGGUGAAGAUUUUAAUAUAUUACUUAUAUGCUUCAAAUUUUAUUUAUGAAAAAAUAUGUAUAUCUGUAAUCAGUUGUUAAGUGAAUGGCACUAAAAGUAUCGAGAACAGCUUUCUUUCCCAGGGGUGAAGGAUGGCGCUCGGGGGUGACUCCUAAGCUCAGCGUGGAAGCUUUUCCCUGUCCUGACCCGAUGGAGCAGCCGGUAAGUGAAGAGCACAGCUGGAAGCAGAGACACCUUAUGACUCAAACUGGGCAAACAAUCGGAACGUCAUGCAGAAGGAAUGGCCUGACUCCUGCAGUGCAGAUUGGAGGCCCCAGAACUCCUAUGAACUACUGAGAGUCUACUGGUUUUUAACUUGUUCCUCUGUCUACUGUGUGUUUGGGGGUGACAUCUAAAUUCCAUUUCUUCUUCUUGUUUAAAUGGUGCAGAGAGAAAGGUUGCCCAGACAUCCACCAGCUUACUGUGUUGACAGAUUUGGGAGCAGCUUUUGAUGAAGUUCCACCCAUGAGGGUCCAUGUGGCAAGUAGGGCCACAGGGCAGCACCUGGUUACAACUUGCUGGUGGGUUUUAUGUUGUGCAAUACUAGGAGGAGGAGGCAGGUGAUCUAUGCUGAUCUAUGAUCACCUGCUUCAGUAGAAUUUUUCUGUAGAGUGUUGUUUGAAUUUUGAGCCUCCAGGUUAGAGGCUCCAAGCAGACAAAGAAGAAAGUUUGUAGACACAAUAUUCUAACAUUGCACAAGUUGAUGAGAUAUCAAGUUUUGAAUAUUAUUCAGGAAGCACUUUGGAGAAUGUGGGAGUCCUACUGUUUUGCACUAGUCUGUAAUUUGUUACCUCUCCCCAUUCGAUAAUAUAGUAACUCAGAAUUUUCAUAUAAAAUUGAAUUCUACUCAUUAGAGUACUUUUUAAAAGUACAGCAGAAAGAAAAGAAGUGGAACAUAAGCAUUCAAGAUUAAUAUUUGAUUCUCUAUCUCUUAACUGUAGAUUUUAUUGGCCUGUUUUUUUUUUCUAAAUAAUUCUUUAAAACUUGACUGGAACAUGCCUCUGCAUUUCUGAGUGUAGAAAUUAAAUGAAGCCACUCACAGUCCUUUGAUUUCCCACUGAAGAUACCCCAAAGGAUGCAAGUGCCUACAGUAUUAUCAGGAGGAGAACAUGAAAAUAUUAAGACAAAAAUCCUCAGCAGUUGUUCUCCACCCCUUCUCCACCUCCACCAGCAAGGAGAAGUCAAUCUACACUUUUUUCUCAUGUUCUAAAGUCUUAGAAUACUGCUGGAUUGUUGAGCAUGAGACAGAGCAAAGGUUAGAUACACAAGGUACAAGUUCAUAGGAGCACAAUUCCUUGAUUCAGGGAAAGUAGCACAGAAUGCAAUUUGAAAACUACAGGCUUAGGACUCUGUGCCAAAAAUCUCUAUUUUAAAUGAAAAUAUUUAUAUAAAAAUACAUUUAUUCUGCUUAACACAAAUUAAAACUGACAUAAAAUUUUAUGAUAAUAACAUGAUUCAAGAAAUGUGAUGUAGAUUUUUGAGAAUGCCAAAAAUCAGGUUUCAGAAAAGCUACAGUAUGAAAUCUGAAAAGCAACAGAAAUUGAAAGUGACCUUAAAGAAUAAAUUUCCUAAUUUUUCCCAGUUUCCUAUGUUUAUAACUAUUAUAAAGAGUUUAACUUUCUGGAACUGAAGGAGAAAACAUGAAAAUGUUUAUAUUGCUUCUUGUUAAGCAGGUAGACCAAAUUCCGCUUUCAGUAAUUCAUCCAUACAGAAUUUGGAUGACUAUGUAUAAAGGAAAACUUAAAUCUUAAUUAUUAUCAGUUUAAAUUUUUUUUGUUUGUUGAAUGACAAAGGCAAUAAAAAUAAAUUUGACUUUAGCUUUUUUUCUAUACUUUCCUCUUUUUGUAAUUCUUAAAUUCUAGUCACUAGUCAUUAUGAGAGUAUUGACUAAAUAUUUUCACAAUCUAAAUAUUGUCACAAUCUAAAUUUCUGUAGUAGAGAGAGCCGUAGCCCUUUGUAAAGGCUUUCGUUCGUCCAAACAACACUUGAUCCAACCAAAGUUCCAAUGUGACUGUGGAUCUUUGAUAGGUCUUUGGUGUUGGUUGUAACAAAAUUUGAUUUGAACUACCUAUAAAUGAAAAGUCGGGGUUUAUUACUUUAUAUGUAAUGCUGAGAGGAGACUGUUGGGAACAGUUAUGUCAAUGAGCAAACUAGAAAUUGGCUUCAAAGUCUAAUACUUUUAAAAGCAUGUGUUUUGUGUAUAUGCUCACAAAAUGUCUGUGAAGAGAUUUCUUUCAGCUUUUGCUCAGCUUUAUGGUGGGGUGUACUGUUUUAUCUGGGCGGUGAGGGUAUUGAUUUACAUAAAAACUGUAGACAAACACAGUACGAGUCUCAGCACGUUUUGCAUUUAUUGUACUGCCCAAAUUGUUUUUAUGUUAAAAGUCACGUUUCAUAAUCUGCAAUAUUUUUGUCAAAGUGCACACUGUACUUUCUUCUUAAAAACGUGAUUAAAGAGAUCACUUUGUCCGGAUGAAGCAGCUGUUGGCAUUAUCCGCUGAGGCUUGAACACCA